CUUACUUUUUUCUUUAGAUGGUUUUAUUUACUUUUUUUUAUUAGUUUUGGGGAAGUGAUGAGAAUCUCACAAUUGCGGGAAUUUCUAGCUCGCAGAUGCUGAGUCUUUUCCGUGGUUAACGUCAUGAUAGUAAUAACGAGAAUGCUGAUACUAAUAACGACAGCCCUUAUAUGUUGGAAAAUGCAUAAAAAUAAAGAUAAACAAGGAAUGGAGAAUGAAAACAUGGCACUGUCCCUACUGCGCUAUUAUCUGUGGAUGUGAUUUACUUCAGCUCUUCCAAACAGACAACCGUCUGAACAACACAAGGAUGUGGCCAGCACCCAAACAGACCACACUCCUCUGAAGCAGGAGGGCAGUCAUCAUUCACCAGUUACUCCUAAUGUCGAAAAUGUAUGCAAUUUGGACCAUGGCGCCUGAUCGAGGUAAACUAAAUAGCACCAUGAACUCACAGCAUAGUGAACUAUCCACACGGCAGUCGGAGACAAGCACAUUUGCAAUUUUUCUGAGAUUUGCCAGAAUCGGAAUGACUCAAUCCACGGAAGAUAAUGGAUGUGAGUAUGGGAAAUGGAGCUGUAAGAACGGAAGGCCGCCUUGUUUCCUCUGUUCCCAUGCCUGUGGGGUUCACGCUUUAAUUCAGGAAGAUGUGCCAAGGAAAGGCGUUGCUCUCACCGGUCAGGGUCCAAGGCUCCGGGCCACCAUUAAUGUCUCGUUGCACACCAAUGGCGUUCCCGGGGAGCUUAUCUGGCACUGCAAGAGCAAAGCAGCUCUGCUGCAAAUCCACCUGACUCAGAAAGCUCUUGACGACCCAGAGCAGUUGGUUCUGCUGUCCUCCACCUCACACUUUCCGGAGGACUUGGGACAGUACGUACACGUGAAUCCGCAUGUGCCCACACUUGGGGCUGUACAUACACGUGUAUCUUCAUGUGCUCACACUUGGGGCUGUACACACACGUGUAUCUUCAUGUGCUCACACUUGGGGCUGUACACACAUGUGUACAUACUUGGGGCUGUAUGUACAUGUGCCCACACUUGGGGCUGUACGUACAUGUGUAUCUGUGUCUGCCUACACUUGGGACUGCGGAUUGUAACACACCAAGUGACUGCAAGGGACCCCAACAGAGGAUAGUGCAGCUCUGCGUUCUCAUUUCUGACACUCUCUCUUCUUAUUUCAACAGUGACUUCAUUUGUGUGAAACAGUCUAAUGUCAGUGUGGUUCUUCUAUGACACCUGGUAUGUUAUUGUCACAUUGUCAUCAGGAUCAUAUAAGAAAAUGUCGAUUGGGAAGAAACUCUGCAGCUAGUUAAAAAAUUCUUUUAAGAGGCUCCCUUUCCGUUGAUUCUAAUUCCUGUACACCUACAAGGUCAUUUCUCAUGAGUGAGAUGCUCCUGUCCCUGUCCCACCUUGACAGGGGGUGGGAGAAGGCCUCUGAGGUCUCAGUGCUCACCCAGGCCUGCCCCAUACUUUUAUCUGUGGUAUCAGCCAUUUAUUACCACCAGGUCUCCGGUUUAGUCCCCUGCUGACUUGGCAUCUCUGGAUUACAUACACUGCCUUACAAUUUUCAGGUCAAUUUGUGAUUGAAGGGAUGAUUAUUUUUGUGCUUAUCUUUGGGAAUGACAUUUACUUUAACUGGGGUCUGCAGAAACUUUAGAGUGGACUUCCGGCCUGGCUUGGUGCAGUCCCUCCAUCUACAGGCUUGGAUUUUUCAGGGUCUCAGAGUUGGUCUGGCUCAAGAACACUGACUCGUGUUAGCACAUCUCAGAGGAGACUGACACAGGAAACCAGAGUGCCAGUUCAUUAAUUUACAGUGAGUAAUAUAAGUGUCAAGUGGACCAGAUGUUGGCUUCAUCCUGACCAACACAUUCUCUCCCUGUAGGCAAGCUACUUGGGAAGUCAAACAAUCAGAAGGAUGCUUGGGGAACAGGCAGUCAGAACAGGAGCACGGAGUUUGAUGAUUCCAACGUCCAGCCACACGAAUGGUACACAAAGGCUGUUCAGACCCCUCAUUGGAAGCCGGAACAGGAGCUGUUGCUCUGUAAUUAGCGUAUCACGUGCAACUCCGAGCUGCUCACCUUCUGAUACCUGGCUGCCCUCACCUUGUCUGCAUCCCAAGGCACAAUGGAAGUGAGCGUCUGGCCUGCCAUGGGUGUACGGGGUAUGUGGUGCAAUAUUUGUGAGCAUCAUGUACACAAAUAGUGUACACAAAUGGUAUUUGGCUAAGAGACACUAGCCACAAAAUAAAAAAUAUACCUAAGAAUUAUCUGAUAUGAAUUUGCACAUCCCUAUCAACCAGCAAAAUGUUACAAUCAACCAGCAAUACACAGUUUUUUAGUAACGCAGAUCAUUGCCAGCUUCACUCAUGUUAAUUCGUGGCUCAGGUCCGCAGUAAGAUAUACCUGUUAGGCAG